UGAGCCAAGAUUGUGCCACUACCCUCUAGCCUGGGCAACAAAGUGAGACUCUGUCUCAAAACAAACAAAAAAAGACCCCCUUCGGCAGCAGUAGACGUGACAGUUAACCCACCUCGAGCACUCGGCCAUCGAUCUGCCUUCCUCCUGGACAGCAGACACUGGGCAACAUCAAGUGUGCAGUCCCUAAAAUACAUCAAAGCUGGGAUCACUUCCCCUCCUGGGUAGCUUGGGACCUCCAGUCCCUUUGGAAGAGUUGGUUCAUUUUCUUUUUAGGAGGCCUUCUUGAAUCUCUAGUCGUCGUCAGGCUUAGGUCACACUACCCAUGCACUGAUCAGCCCUGCCACGUGGGGGAGGCUCCAAAAAAUGAAGCGGUUCCAGGGGUGCCAAGGUUCAGAGCAGAGUCUUGAGAGCCUGAGGGGCAGGAGGAGGCAAAGGUCUCUGAGGACGAAGGGGUUUGGCCACAGUCCCGGAAGAUCUCAGGUCGUGGGGCUUCUGUGAGCGGGCACAUCCCCUGUGCCUGUGUGAUUGUGAGCUUGUGUGCUUGUGUGGUUGGGGGUCCUUCCUGGAGGAGGCAUCUAGGUUGAGGGCCCCAGGCCGGGAAUGGGGUGGGGCCUGUCGUCAAGGAAGGGACUCAGCCCUGGAGGUUUCUGUGAGAGCUCAAGCCACAGGAGCCACAAGAUAAGAGGAGUGUGGCUGCAGAACCCAGGUGGCAGGGCUUUCCUCAGGCCCCUUACUCCUGACCUGGACGAGGCCGGGGCUUCCUCAAGGAGGUAGGAGGUAUCCUGGCCAGCAGAUCAGCCAGAAGCUCUAGGAGGAAGGCUCUCUGACUGCCACCCCUGCCUGCCUGCCCGGCCCUGCACAACAUGCAGCCCUCCGGCCUCGAGGGUCCCGGCACGUUUGGUCGGUGGCCUCUGCUGAGUCUGCUGCUCCUGCUGCUGCUGCUCCAGCCUGUAACCUGUGCCUACACCACGCCAGGCCCCCCCAGAGCCCUCACCACGCUGGGCGCCCCCAGAGCCCACACCAUGCCGGGCACCUACGCUCCCUCGACCACACUCAGUAGUCCCAGCACCCAGGGCCUGCAAGAGCAGGCACGGGCCCUGAUGCGGGACUUCCCGCUCGUGGACGGCCACAACGACCUGCCCCUGGUCCUAAGGCAGGUUUACCAGAAAGGGCUACAGGAUGUUAACCUGCGCAAUUUCAGCUACGGCCAGACCAGCCUGGACAGGCUUAGAGAUGGCCUCGUGGGCGCCCAGUUCUGGUCAGCCUAUGUGCCAUGCCAGACCCAGGACCGGGAUGCCCUGCGCCUCACCCUGGAGCAGAUUGACCUCAUACGCCGCAUGUGUGCCUCCUAUUCUGAGCUGGAGCUUGUGACCUCGGCUAAAGCUCUGAACGACACUCAGAAAUUGGCCUGCCUCAUCGGUGUAGAGGGUGGCCACUCGCUGGACAAUAGCCUCUCCAUCUUACGUACCUUCUACAUGCUGGGAGUGCGCUACCUGACGCUCACCCACACCUGCAACACACCCUGGGCAGAGAGCUCCGCUAAGGGCGUCCACUCCUUCUACAACAACAUCAGCGGGCUGACUGACUUUGGUGAGAAGGUGGUGGCAGAAAUGAACCGCCUGGGCAUGAUGGUAGACUUAUCCCAUGUCUCAGAUGCUGUGGCACGGCGGGCCCUGGAAGUGUCACAGGCACCUGUGAUCUUCUCCCACUCGGCUGCCCGGGGUGUGUGCAACAGUGCUCGGAAUGUUCCUGAUGACAUCCUGCAGCUUCUGAAGAAGAACGGUGGCGUCGUGAUGGUGUCUUUGUCCAUGGGAGUAAUACAGUGCAACCCAUCAGCCAAUGUGUCCACUGUGGCAGAUCACUUCGACCACAUCAAGGCUGUCAUUGGAUCCAAGUUCAUCGGGAUUGGUGGAGAUUAUGAUGGGGCCGGCAAGGAAUCAGGUCUGAAACCCACUAGCUGGUGGCCACACAGAUUCCCUCAGGGGCUGGAAGACGUGUCCACAUACCCGGUCCUGAUAGAGGAGUUGCUGAGUCGUGGCUGGAGUGAGGAAGAGCUUCAGGGUGUCCUUCGUGGAAACCUGCUGCGGGUCUUCAGACAAGUGGAAAAGGUACAGGAAGAAAACAAAUGGCAAAGCCCCUUGGAGGACAAGUUCCCGGAUGAGCAGCUGAGCAGUUCCUGCCACUCCGACCUCUCACGUCUGCGUCAGAGACAGAGUCUGACUUCAGGCCAGGAACUCACUGAGAUUCCCAUACACUGGACAGCCAAGUUACCAGCCAAGUGGUCAGUCUCAGAGUCCUCCCCCCACAUGGCCCCAGUCCUUGCAGUUGUGGCCACCUUCCCAGUCCUUAUUCUGUGGCUCUGAUGACCCAGUUAGUCCUGCCAGAUGUCACUGUAGCAAGCCACAGACACCCCACAAAGUUCCCCUGUUGUGCAGGCACAAAUAUUUCCUGAAAUAAAUGUUUUGGACAUAGAAACAGA